GCAUGCGCAUAGCUAACCGCACCCGGUUCAGCUCGCCUUUCUUGGCCAGAGGCGCCGGUUGGACUCACGGGCGGGGCAUGAUGGUGGUGGGUACGGGCACCUCGCUGGCGCUCUCCUCCCUCCUGUCCCUGCUGCUCUUUGCUGGGAUGCAGAUGUACAGCCGUCAGCUGGCCUCCACCGAGUGGCUCACCAUCCAGGGCGGCCUGCUUGGUUCGGGUCUCUUCGUGUUCUCGCUCACUGCCUUCAAUAAUCUGGAGAAUCUUGUCUUUGGCAAAGGAUUCCAAGCAAAGAUCUUCCCUGAGAUUCUCCUGUGCCUCCUGUUGGCUCUCUUUGCAUCUGGCCUCAUCCACCGAGUCUGUGUCACCACCUGCUUCAUCUUCUCCAUGGUUGGUCUGUACUACAUCAACAAGAUCUCCUCCACCCUGUACCAGGCAGCAGCUCCAGUCCUCACACCAGCCAAGGUCACAGGCAAGAGCAAGAAGAGAAACUGACCCUGAAUGUUCAAUAAAGUUGAUUCUUUGUA